GCUCAAAAGUUCAGAAGUUUUCCCAAUGCUUCCUUAAGCGGCUGGCGCGCGAGAGACCGAGAAAAGGUGACGCGGGGCCCGGGCAGGCGGCCGGCGCGCGGCCCCCCCCCCCCCCGCCCUGGUUAUUUGGCCGCCUUCGCCGGCAGCUCAGGGCAGAGUCUCCUGGAAGGCGCAGGCAGUGUGGCGAGAAGGGCGCCUGCUUGUUCUUUCUUUUUGUCUGCUUUCCCCCGUUUGCGCCUGGAAGCUGCGCCGCGAGUUCCUGCAAGGCGGUCUGCCGCGGCCGGGCCCGGCCUUCUCCCCUCGCAGCGACCCCGCCUCGCGGCCGCGCGGGCCCCGAGGUAGCCCGAGGCGCCGGAGGAGCCAGCCCCAGCGAGCGCCGGGAGAGGCGGCAGCGCAGCCGGACGCACAGCGCAGCGGGCCGGCACCAGCUCGGCCGGGCCCGGACUCGGACUCGGCGGCCGGCGCGGCGCGGCCCGGCCCGAGCGAGGGUGGGGGGCGGCGGGCGGCGCGGGGCGGCGGCGAGCGGGGGCCAUGCAGGCGCGCUACUCCGUGUCCAGCCCCAACUCCCUGGGAGUGGUGCCCUACCUCGGCGGCGAGCAGAGCUACUACCGCGCGGCGGCCGCGGCGGCCGGGGGCGGCUACACCGCCAUGCCGGCCCCCAUGAGCGUGUACUCGCACCCUGCGCACGCCGAGCAGUACCCGGGCGGCAUGGCCCGCGCCUACGGGCCCUACACGCCGCAGCCGCAGCCCAAGGACAUGGUGAAGCCGCCCUAUAGCUACAUCGCGCUCAUCACCAUGGCCAUCCAGAACGCCCCGGACAAGAAGAUCACCCUGAACGGCAUCUACCAGUUCAUCAUGGACCGCUUCCCCUUCUACCGGGACAACAAGCAGGGCUGGCAGAACAGCAUCCGCCACAACCUCUCGCUCAACGAGUGCUUCGUCAAGGUGCCGCGCGACGACAAGAAGCCGGGCAAGGGCAGCUACUGGACGCUGGACCCGGACUCCUACAACAUGUUCGAGAACGGCAGCUUCCUGCGGCGGCGGCGGCGCUUCAAGAAGAAGGACGCGGUGAAGGACAAGGAGGAGAAGGACAGGCUGCACCUCAAGGAGCCGCCCCCGCCCGGCCGCCAGCCCCCGCCCGCGCCGCCGGAGCAGGCCGACGGCAACGCGCCCGGUCCGCAGCCGCCGCCCGUGCGCAUCCAGGACAUCAAGACCGAGAACGGUACGUGCCCCUCGCCGCCCCAGCCCCUGUCCCCGGCCGCCGCCCUGGGCAGCGGCAGCGCCGCCGCGGUGCCCAAGAUCGAGAGCCCCGACAGCAGCAGCAGCAGCCUGUCCAGCGGGAGCAGCCCCCCGGGCAGCCUGCCGUCGGCGCGGCCGCUCAGCCUGGACGGUGCGGAUUCCGCGCCGCCGCCGCCCGCGCCCUCCGCCCCGCCGCCGCACCAUAGCCAGGGCUUCAGCGUGGACAACAUCAUGACGUCGCUGCGGGGGUCGCCGCAGAGCGCGGCCGCGGAGCUCAGCUCCGGCCUUCUGGCCUCGGCGGCCGCGUCCUCGCGCGCGGGGAUCGCACCCCCGCUGGCGCUCGGCGCCUACUCGCCCGGCCAGAGCUCCCUCUACAGCUCCCCCUGCAGCCAGACCUCCAGCGCGGGCAGCUCGGGCGGCGGCGGCGGCGGCGCGGGGGCCGCGGGGGGCGCGGGCGGCGCCGGGACCUACCACUGCAACCUGCAAGCCAUGAGCCUGUACGCGGCCGGCGAGCGCGGGGGCCACUUGCAGGGCGCGCCCGGGGGCGCGGGCGGCUCGGCCGUGGACGACCCCCUGCCCGACUACUCUCUGCCUCCGGUCACCAGCAGCAGCUCGUCGUCCCUGAGUCACGGCGGCGGCGGCGGCGGCGGCGGGGGAGGCCAGGAGGCCGGCCACCACCCUGCGGCCCACCAAGGCCGCCUCACCUCGUGGUACCUGAACCAGGCGGGCGGAGACCUGGGCCACUUGGCGAGCGCGGCGGCGGCGGCGGCGGCCGCAGGCUACCCGGGCCAGCAGCAGAACUUCCACUCGGUGCGGGAGAUGUUCGAGUCACAGAGGAUCGGCUUGAACAACUCUCCAGUGAACGGGAAUAGUAGCUGUCAAAUGGCCUUCCCUUCCAGCCAGUCUCUGUACCGCACGUCCGGAGCUUUCGUCUACGACUGUAGCAAGUUUUGACACACCCUCAAAGCCGAACUAAAUCGAACCCCAAAGCAGGAAAAGCUAAAGGAACCCAUCAAGGCAAAAUCGAAACUAAAAAAAAAAAAUCCAAUUAAAAAAAACCCCUGAGAAUAUUCACCACACCAGCGAACAGAAUAUCCCUCCAAAAAUUCAGCUCACCAGCACCAGCACGAAGAAAACUCUAUUUUCUUAACCGAUUAAUUCAGAGCCACCUCCACUUUGCCUUGUCUAAAUAAACAAACCCGUAAACUGUUUUAUACAGAGACAGCAAAAUCUUGGUUUAUUAAAGGACAGUGUUACUCCAGAUAACACGUAAGUUUCUUCUUGCUUUUCAGAGACCUGCUUUCCCCUCCUCCCGUCUCCCCUCUCUUGCCUUCUUCCUUGCCUCUCACCUGUAAGAUAUUAUUUUAUCCUAUGUUGAAGGGAGGGGGAAAGUCCCCGUUUAUGAAAGUCGCUUUCUUUUUAUUCAUGGACUUGUUUUAAAAUGUAAAUUGCAACAUAGUAAUUUAUUUUUAAUUUGUAGUUGGAUGUCGUGGACCAAACGCCAGAAAGUGUUCCCAAAACCUGACGUUAAAUUGCCUGAAACUUUAAAUUGUGCUUUUUUUCUCAUUAUAAAAAGGGAAACUGUAUUAAUCUUAUUCUAUCCUCUUUUCUUUCUUUUUGUUGAACAUAUUCAUUGUUUGUUUAUUAAUAAAUUACCAUUCAGUUUGAAUGAGACCUAUAUGUCUGGAUACUUUAAUAGAGCUUUAAUUAUUACGAAAAAAGAUUUCAGAGAUAAAACACUAGAAGUUACCUAUUCUCCACCUAAAUCUCUGAAAAAUGGAGAAACCCUCUGACUAGUCCAUGUCAAAUUUUACUAAAAGUCUUUUUGUUUAGAUUUAUUUUCCUGCAGCAUCUUCUGCAAAAUGUACUAUAUAGUCAGCUUGCUUUGAGGCUAGUAAAAAGAUAUUUUUCUAAACAGAUUGGAGUUGGCAUAUAAACAAAUACGUUUUCUCACUAAUGACAGUCCAUGAUUCGGAAAUUUUAAGCCCAUGAAUCAGCCGCGGUCUUACCACGGUGAUGCCUGUGUGCCGAGAGAUGGGACUGUGCGGCCAGAUAUGCACAGAUAAAUAUUUGGCUUGUGUAUUCCAUAUAAAAUUGCAGUGCAUAUUAUACAUCCCUGUGAGCCAGAUGCUGAAUAGAUAUUUUCCUAUUAUUUCAGUCCUUUAUAAAAGGAAAAAUAAACCAGUUUUUAAAUGUAUGUAUAUAAUUCUCCCCCAUUUACAAUCCUUCAUGUAUUACAUAGAAGGAUUGCUUUUUUAAAAAUAUACUGCGGGUUGGAAAGGGAUAUUUAAUCUUUGAGAAACUAUUUUAGAAAAUAUGUUUGUAGAACAAUUAUUUUUGAAAAAGAUUUAAAGCAAUAACAAGAAGGAAGGCGAGAGGAGCAGAACAUUUUGGUCUAGGGUGGUUUCUUUUUAAACCAUUUUUUCUUGUUAAUUUACAGUUAAACCUAGGGGACAAUCCGGAUUGGCCCUCCCCCUUUUGUAAAUAACCCAGGAAAUGUAAUAAAUUCAUUAUCUUAGGGUGAUCUGCCCUGCCAAUCAGACUUUGGGGAGAUGGCGAUUUGAUUACAGACGUUCGGGGGGGUGGGGGGCUUGCAGUUUGUUUUGGAGAUAAUACAGUUUCCUGCUAUCUGCCGCUCCUAUCUAGAGGCAACACUUAAGCAGUAAUUGCUGUUGCUUGUUGUCAAAAUUUGAUCAUUGUUAAAGGAUUGCUGCAAAUAAAUACACUUUAAUUUCAGUCAAAAA